AGGCUUGGGAUCCCGGCUGCGGGUUUGGCGGCGCUGCGCCGGCAGGCAGCGAGGCCGGGCGGGCCCUGGGCCCUCGCGCCCCUCCCGCGAGGCCUGUCAUGCAGGGCCCCGCCGGGAACGCGAGCCGGGGACUGCCAGGCGGGCCGCCCUCCACAGUCGCGUCCGGGGCGGGCCGCUGCGAGAGCGGCGCGCUCAUGCACAGCUUCGGCAUCUUCCUGCAGGGGCUGCUCGGCGUCGUGGCCUUCAGCACGUUAAUGCUCAAACGCUUCAGAGAACCAAAGCAUGAAAGACGUCCGUGGAGGAUAUGGUUUUUAGACACUUCCAAACAAGCCAUAGGAAUGCUGUUCAUCCACUUUGCAAAUGUAUACCUAGCAGAUCUCACUGAAGAGGACCCUUGUUCACUGUACCUCAUCAACUUCCUCCUGGACGCCACUGUGGGCAUGCUGCUCAUCUACGUGGGGGUGCGCGCCGUCAGCGUCCUGGUAGAGUGGCAGCAGUGGGAGUCCCUGCGCUUCGGCGAAUAUGGAGACCCUCUGCAGUGUGGAGCCUGGGUCGGGCAGUGCGCUCUUUACAUCGUGAUCAUGAUUUUUGAAAAGUCUGUCGUCUUCAUCGUCCUCCUAAUACUUCAGUGGAAAAAGGUGGCCCUGUUGAAUCCCAUUGAAAACCCAGACUUGAAGCUGGCCAUCGUCAUGCUGAUCGUCCCCUUCUUUGUCAACGCUUUGAUGUUUUGGGUAGUGGACAAUUUCCUCAUGAGAAAGGGGAAGACGAAAGCUAAGCUAGAAGAAAGGGGAGCCAACCAGGACUCGAGGAAUGGGAGCAAGGUCCGCUACCGGAGGGCCGCAUCCCACGAGGAGUCUGAGUCUGAGAUCCUGAUCUCAGCGGAUGAUGAGAUGGAGGAGUCCGACGUGGAGGAGGACCUCCGCAGACUGACCCCCCUCAAGCCUGUGAAGAAAAAGAAGCACCGCUUUGGGCUACCCGCUGGUGCUCAGGAAGCCCCUAUCAAGAAGAAGCGCCCCCCUGUGAAGGACGAGGACCUGAAGGGGGCCCGAGGAAACCUGACCAAGAACCAGGAAAUCAAGUCCAAGACCUACCAGGUCAUGCGAGAGUGUGAGCAAGCUGGCUCGGCCGCCCCGUCGGUGUUCAGCCGCACCCGCACAGGUACCGAGACUGUCUUUGAGAAGCCCAAAGCCGGACCCACCAAGAGUGUCUUCGGCUGAGAAGUGUGCGCCACUCCCCUUGCUGCCCGAAUGCUCGGAAACAGGAGCCUUUCCCAGGAACUCUUUUUUAUGCCAGAACGCUUCCUCUCCCCUGCUGUCUCUGGGGCUGCCACCCUCCCCCACAGUCCAGGCCCUUCAGCCAAGGGCUCUGCACCAGCACCUUGGAAGCACCAAUAAAGAGGAUGCCCACGUGGCCCCAGCAA